AGUCUUUCUUGACCGUAUAGAUAAUAGGCCUUUUGCCAUGUCUGGGCGUGGCAAGCAGGGAGGCAAAGCUCGCGCCAAGGCCAAGACCCGCUCUUCUCGGGCCGGGCUUCAGUUUCCCGUAGGCCGAGUGCAUCGCCUGCUCCGCAAAGGCAACUAUGCGGAGCGGGUCGGUGCUGGAGCGCCGGUGUACCUGGCGGCGGUGCUGGAGUACCUGACCGCCGAGAUCCUGGAGCUGGCUGGCAACGCGGCCCGCGACAACAAGAAGACUCGCAUCAUCCCGCGUCACCUCCAGCUGGCCAUCCGCAACGAUGAGGAGCUCAACAAGCUUCUGGGCAAAGUCACCAUCGCACAGGGUGGCGUCCUGCCCAACAUCCAGGCCGUGCUACUGCCCAAGAAGACCGAGAGCCACCACAAGGCGAAGGGCAAGUAGAAGCCUGGAUUAGUUUGCAGCAACUCAAUCCCAAAGGAACCAAAGGCUCUUUUCAGAGCCACCUA